AGUCCCCCGGUUUCCCUGGAGACCAGGCGGAAGCGGCCGGAAGUAGCGCUGCGGUUGGCAGCGGCGGGAUGGAGAAGCUGGGGGUGGAGCCGGAGGAGGAAGGCGGCGGCGACGACGACGAGGAAGACGCCGAGGCCUGGGCCAUGGAACUGGCGGACGUGGGGGCGGCAGCCAGCUCGCAGGGAGUUCAUGAUCAAGUGUUGCCCACACCAAAUGCUUCAUCCAGAGUCAUAGUACAUGUGGAUCUGGAUUGCUUUUAUGCACAAGUAGAAAUGAUCUCAAAUCCAGAGCUAAAAGACAAACCUUUAGGGGUUCAACAGAAAUAUUUGGUGGUUACCUGCAACUAUGAAGCUAGGAAACUUGGAGUUAAGAAACUUAUGAAUGUCAGAGAUGCAAAAGAAAAGUGUCCACAGUUGGUAUUAGUUAAUGGAGAAGACCUGACCCGCUACAGAGAAAUGUCUUAUAAGGUUACAGAAUUACUGGAAGAAUUUAGUCCAGUUGUUGAGAGACUUGGAUUUGAUGAAAAUUUUGUGGAUCUAACAGAAAUGGUUGAGAAGAGACUACAGCAGCUGCAAAGUGAUGAACUUUCUGCGGUGACUGUGUCGGGUCAUGUAUACAAUAAUCAGUCUAUAAACCUGCUUGACGUCUUGCACAUCAGACUACUUGUUGGAUCUCAGAUUGCAGCAGAGAUGCGGGAAGCCAUGUAUAAUCAGUUGGGGCUCACUGGCUGUGCUGGAGUGGCUUCUAAUAAACUGUUGGCAAAAUUAGUUUCUGGUGUCUUUAAACCAAAUCAACAAACAGUCUUAUUACCUGAAAGUUGUCAACAUCUUAUUCAUAGUUUGAAUCACAUAAAGGAAAUACCUGGUAUUGGCUAUAAAACUGCCAAAUGUCUUGAAGCACUGGGUAUCAAUAGUGUGCGUGAUCUCCAAACCUUUUCACCCAAAAUUUUAGAAAAAGAAUUAGGAAUUUCAGUUGCUCAGCGUAUCCAAAAGCUCAGUUUUGGAGAGGAUAACUCCCCUGUGAUACUCUCAGGACCACCUCAGUCCUUUAGUGAAGAAGAUUCAUUUAAAAAAUGUUCAUCUGAAGUUGAAGCUAAAAAUAAGAUUGAAGAACUACUUGCUAGUCUUUUAAACAGAGUAUGCCAAGAUGGAAGGAAGCCUCAUACAGUGAGAUUAAUAAUCCGUCGGUAUUCCUCUGAGAAGCACUAUGGUCGUGAGAGUCGUCAGUGCCCUAUUCCUUCACAUGUAAUUCAGAAAUUAGGGACAGAACUAUGAAUUGAAGAAAGUGAAAUCAGUAUGCUGCCACCCUGCCACUUCUUCUUGAAAUCUGGAAAGCUGGAGAAGUUACUGACAAUUGUAACCCAGUGAUAAGGAACCAGGAAUUGAGAAGCUGCUGUUGCCUCUGUUGUUGAUGCAUCUACCUCUUGGCACACAAGAGUCUGGUAGUUGGACACUGGAACACAGAAAAGAAGACUCACAUAUCCUUGUUUUUGCUAGCCAUCAGAAAUGGCAAUAAAAUAAUAAUAAUAAUGAAGAAACAUGGCUUCUGCUUCACUAAGAAAGUACUAUUGAAUUACUAUUGAAAUUACUAUUGAAUUUUAAAAAGUGGUCAGUAUAGUAUAUUUGUGUCAUAGUGGUCAUUCCUUUUUGUUUCAAAUUACCAACUUGUAUUCUAAUAAAGUUUAGCCAAUAGUUGAUUUAUCUAAACCAAACCUAUGUAGAUACAUGUAUACUGAGACAGAACAAUUUGUGAUGUUGACAGAAGAAUAUUUCAUCUAUUUAGGCUUAGCCAGACUAUAGUGUUCUACUUCAAUUGUCAUCAACUUUUUUGAUAUAACACCCUAGCAGUGAAAAAAACUUGGGAGGUACACACUCACAGAAUCUGUAUAUUUACUAAAGAUGCACCAAAGUUUAGGUUUAGCCUUAGUAUGCACUUCCUUGGUGUUUGGGUGGCCGAAUAAUCAAAUAACUACAUCAGCAUCAAUUUGUGGCAUCCCAUGAAAUUGUGCACAAAAUUAUCAUGUUCCUCACAUAGUUUACAUCAUAUCUAAUCAGGAUUAAUGAUUCUAGCCAUAAAAAUAGGGCAUCACAUUUAGAUUUAUUAUUAACAUCUGAAUAUUCACUUUCUUUUUUUAACUUUUAUUUUAGAAUUGAGGGAUACGUGUGCAGGUUUGUUACAGAGAUAUAUUGCAUGAUGCUGAUAUUUGGAGUACAAAUGAAUCCAUCACCCAGAUAGUGAGCAUAGUAUCCAAUAGAUAGUUUUUCAACCCUUGAUCCCCUCUCUCCUUCUCCCUUAUAUUCCCCCCCAGCGUCUGUUGUUUCCAUCUUUACAUCCAUGCAUACCCAAUGUUUAGCUCCCACUUAUAAGUGAGAAAACGCAGUAUUUGAUUUUCUGUUUCUGUGUUUUUUGCUUAGGAUAAUGGUUUCCAGUGGCAUCCAUGUUGCUGCAAAGGACAUGACUUUGUUCUUUUUUAUGGCUGUGUAGUAUUCCAUGGUGUAUAUAUGCCAUAUUAUCUUUAUCGAGUAUAUCAUUGAUGGGCACCUGGGUUGAUUCCUAGGUGUUCAUAUGUCUUUGCUCUUGUGAAUAGCGCUGCAGUGAACAUAUGGGUGCAUGUGUCUUUUUGCUGGAAUCAUUUAUUUUCCUUUGGGUAUAUACCCAGGAGUGGGAUUCCUGGGUUGAAUGAUUGUUCAGUUCUUUGAGGAAUCUCCAAACUGCUUUCCACAGUGGCUGAACUAAUUUACAUUCUCACCAACAGUGUGUAAGUAUUCCCUUUUCUCUGUAGCCUCACCAGCACCUGUUAUUUUUGACUUUUUAACAAAAGCCAUUCUGACUGGUGUGAGUUGGUAUUUCAUUGUGAUUUUGGAUUGCAUUUCUCUGAUAAUUAGUGAUAAGCAUUUUUUUCAUAUGUUUAUUAGCUGCUUGUAUGUCUUCUUUUGAGAAGUGUCUGUUUAUGUCCUUUGCCCACUUUUUAAUGGGGUUAUUUGUUGUUUGCUUGUUGAUUUAAAUUCCUUAUAGAUCCUGGAUAUUAGGCCUUUGUUGGAUGCAUAGUUUGGAGAUAUUUUCUCCCAUUCUGUAGCUUGUCUGUUUACACCUUUGAUAGUUUCUCUUGCUGUGCAGAAACUCUUUAGUUUAAUUAGGUCCCACUUGUCAAUUUUUGUUUUCAUUGUAAUUGCUUUUGAGGACUUAGCCAUAAACUCUUUGCCAAUGCCAAUAUCGAGAUGGGUGUUUCCUAGAUUUUCUUCUAAGAAUUUUGUAGUUUGAUGGCUUACAUUUAAGUCUAAUCCAUCUUGAGUUAAUUUUGUGUAUGGUGAUAGGUGGGGGUCCAGUUGCAUUCUUCUGCAUAUGGAUAGCCAGUUAUCCCAGCACCAUGUAUUGAAUAGGCAGUUCUUUCUCUAUUGCUUACAUUUAUCAACUUUGACAAAGAUCAGAUGGUUGUAGGUAUGUGGCUUUAUUUCUGAGUUCUUUUACUCUGCUCCAUUGGUGUAUAUGUCUGUUUUUUAACCAGUAACUUUCUAUUUUCGUUUCUGUAACCUUAUAAUACAUUAUACUUCGAAGUCAAGUAAUAUGAUGUCCCCAGCUUUGUUCUUUUUGCUUAGGAUUGCUUUGGCUAUUUGGGCUUUUUUUUGGUUUUGUAUGAAUUUUAGAAUAGUUUUUCUAAUUUUGUGAAAAAUGACAUUGGUAGUUUGAUAGGAAUAUCAUUGAAUCUGUAAAUUACUCUGGGCACUAUUACCAUUUUAAUGAUAUUCAUUCAUCCAAUCAAUGAGCAUGGAAUGUGUUUCCAUUUAUUUGUGUCAUCUCUGAUUUCUUUGAACAGUGUUUUGUAAUUCUCAUUGUAGAGAUUUUUCACCUCCCUGCUUAUGUGUAUUCCUAGGCAUUUAGUUCUUUUUGUAGCUAUUGUGAAUGGGAUUGUGUUCUUGAUUUGGCUGUCAGUUUUGAUGUUGUUGGUAUGUAGGAAUACUACUGAUUUUUGUACACUGAUUUUGUAUCCUGAAACUUUGCUGAAGUUAUCAGAUAUAGGAACUUUUUGGCAGAGAUUAUGGGGGUUUCUAGAUAUAUAAUCAUAUUGUCUGCAAACGGGGAUAGUUUGACUUCCUCUCUGGCUGUUUGGAUACCCUUUAUUCCUUUCUCUUCCUUGAUUGCUGUGGCCAGGAUUUCCAGUACUGUUGAUUAGGAGUGGUGAGAGAGGGCAUCCUUGCCUUGUUCUGAUUUUCAAAGGGAAUGCGUCCAGCUUUUGCCCAUUCAGUAUAAUGUUGGCUGUGUAUUUGUCAUAGAUGGUUUUUAUUAUUUUGACAUAUGUUCCUUUGAUGCCUAGUUUGUUGAGGGCUUUUAUCAUGAGGGGAUGUUGAAUUUUGUCAAAAGCCUCUUCUGGAUCCAUUGAGAUGAUCAUGUGGCUUUUGUUUUUAAUUCUUCCUGGGAUGCAAAGUUGGUUCAACAUAAUAAUUUAUUCACAUUUAUUGAUUUGUAUAUGUUGAACCAACCUUGCAUCCCAGGAAGAAAGCCUAUUUGAUUGUGGUUAAUUAACUUUUUGAUGUUCUGCUGGAUUCAGAUUGUUAGUAUUUUGUUUAUGGUUUUUGCAUCAAUGUUCAUCAGCAAUAUUGGCCUGAAGUUUUCUUUUUUUGUUGUGUCUUUGCCAGUUUUUGGUAUCAGGACGAUGUUUGUUUCAUAAAAUGAGUUAGUGGGGAGUCCCUCCUCCUCAGUUUUCUUUGGAAUAGUUUCAGUAGGAUUGGUGCCAGCUCUUCUUUAUAUGUCUUAUAGAAUUCAGCUGUGAAUCCAUGUGGUCCAGGGCUUUUUUAAAAAAUUAUUACUGACUCAAUUUUGGACUCAUUAGUGGUCAGUUCAGGGUUUCAGUUUCUUCCUGGUUCAAUCUUGAGAUGUUGCAUGCUUCCAGGAAUUUAUUCAUUUCCUCUAGAUUUUCUAGUUUGUGUGCAUAGAGGUGUUCGUAAUGGUCACUGGGUAUCUUCUGUAUUUCUGUGGGAUCAGUUGUAAUGUCAUCUUUGUUUAUUUCUGAUUGUGUUUAUUUGGAUCUUCUUUUUUUCUUUGUUAAUCUGAUUAGUGGUCUAUCAAUCUUGUUUAUUCUUUCAAAGAACCAACUUUUGAUUUCAUUGAUCUUUUUGUAUGGAUUUUUGGGUCUCAGUGUUAUUCUGUUAUGCUCUGAUUUUGGUUAUUUAUUUUUUUAUGCUAGCUUUGCAGUCAGUUUGCUCUUGUUUUUCUAGUUCCUCUUCAUGUAAUGUUAGAUUAUUAAUUUGAGAUCUUUCUAACAUUGAUGUAGGCAUCUAGUGCUAUAAACUUUACUCUUAUGACAUUGCUUCAGCUGCGUCCAAAUAUUUUGGUAUGCUAUGUCUCUAUUUUAUUAAUUUCAAAGAUUUUUGGAUAUCUGCCUUACUUUCAUUGUUUACCUGAAAGCCAUUCAGGAGCAAGUUGUUUAAUUUCCAUGUAAUUAUAUGGUUUUGAGAGAUUUUUUGGUAUUAAUUUCUAUUUUUAUUGCACUGUGGUCUGAGAGUGUGCUUGGUGAUUUCAAUUUUUUUUCAAUUUCUUGAGACUUGCUUUAUGUAUGGCCAAGUAUGUGGUUGAUCUUAGAGUAUGUUUUGUGUGUGGAUGAGAAGAAUGUAUAUUCUGUGGUUGCUGGGUGGAAUAUUCUAUAGAUGUCUAUUAGGUCCAAUUGGUCAAGUGUUUGCUUUAAGUCCAGAAUUUCUUUGUUAAUUUCUACCUUAAUGUACUGUCUAACACUGUCAGUGGGGUGGUGAAGUCUCUAUUACUAUGUGGCUAAGUCUUUUUGUAGGUCUAGAAGUAGUUGUUUUAUGAAUCGGUGCUCCAAUGUUGGGCGCAUAUAUAUUUAGGAUUGUUAAGUCUUCUUGUUGAAUUGAACCCUUUGUCAUUAUAUAAUGCCCUUCUUUGUUCUUUUUGACUGUUUUUGAUUUAAAGUCUGUUUUAUCUGAUACAAAAAUAAUGACCCCUAUUCUUUUUUGUUUUCCAUUUGCAUGAUGGAUCUUUCUCCACCUCUUUACUUUGAGCCUCUGUGUGUCAUUAAUGUGAGAUGGGUUUCUUGAAGACAGCAGACAGUUGGGUCUUGAUUUUUUAUCCAACUUGACAUUUUAUGCAUUUUUUUUUUUUGAGACAGGGUCUUCCUUUGUUGCCUAGACUGGAAUGCAGUGCUGUGCUUAUAGCUCACUGCAGGCUUGAACUCCUAGGCUCAUGCAAUCUUCCUGCCUCAGCCUCCUGAGUAGCUGGGACUACAGGCAUGUACCACCAUGCCUGGCUAAUUUGCUAUUUUUUGUAGAGACAGGAUUGCACUGUGUUGCCCAGACUGGUUUCAAAGUCCUGGGCUCAAGUGAUCUUCCUGCCUUGGCUUCCCAGAAAGUUGGGAUUAUAGGUGUGAGCCACUGCACCAGACAUCUAUGCCUUUUAAGUUGGACAUUUAGACUGUUGACAUUCAAAGUUAAUAUUGGUAUGGGACAUUUUGAUCCUGUCAUCAUGAAUAUGUACUUUCAACUAUGGGUAAACAUUCUAGAUGUUACCUAAUAAAAUCUCAUAAGCUUUUCUUGUGAUUUCAUCAGAGUCUAAAUUUGUGAUUAUUAUUGCAAAGAAAAAUGUUGAUAUAAUUGAAGAUUGUGAAGCUUAUUUUAUGUACAAAACAAUUAUUAACAGCUUACAAAUUAUUGAGAGAGUGGAUUAGCUUGGUCAUUUUAUGAUGUAACAUAUUCUUUUUGAGUCCACAGAAUAAAAUGUGUGGUUAUU